ACACUCAGGAUCUUGCCUUGAGCAGCAUACCAACUCACCACUCCUGACACCAUGAACUACUACGGCAACUACUAUGGAGGCCUGGGCUACGGCUACGGAGGCUUCGAUGACCUGGGCUAUGGCUAUGGCUGUGGAUGUGGCAGCUUCCGCAGACUGGGCUAUGGCGGUGGCUACGGAGGCUACGGAUACGGCUCUGGCUUCGGAGGCUAUGGAUACCGCAGCUGCCGUCCAUCAUGCUAUGGAGGAUAUGGAUUCUCUGGAUUUUAUUGAAAUCCUUCCCUGACAACCUAACAUGAGGGGACAUAAGAAGAUCACCCAAACCUGACUGCAAUAACAAACAAACGAGGUCACCCUGGAUCAAGCCAAGAUCAAGAGCAGUUAGCAUCUAAGAGGUUUAAGAAUACCUAUCAUUCCAUAAUUCUUUGCUUUAUGUCUCUGGAUGUGUCUUACUUGUACCUUUAUAACUGUGGGGUUUCUCUGUUCCU